CCAAGGAUGACCUCAACAACCAACACCAUGUGUGGCAGCUACUACAGAAACUACAAUGGUGGCCAUGGCUAUGGGUGCUGUGGCUACGGAGGCCUGGGCUGUGGUUAUGGCGGCUGUGGCUAUGGGUGCUGUGGCUACGGAGGCCUGGGCUUUGGCUAUGGAGGCCUGGACUGUGGCUAUGGAGGCCUGGGCUGUGGCUAUGGCUCCUUCUGUGGCUGUGGCUACAGAGGCCUGGACUGUGGCUAUGGCUGUGGCUAUGGCUAUGUCUCCCACUCCUUCUGUGGCUGUGGCUAUAGGUGCGGCUCUGGCUAUGGCUCCAGCUUUGGCUACUACUAUUGAGGACACCAUGGGAGACUCUCACCCUCUAUCCUGUGACAUUGCAAUUCACCAAUUCUGAAGCCCACAUGCUCUGAGCCUUUCCCUUGAUUGAUGAUAUCCUGCAGUGGAAGUCUAAUAUGAUCUGUUGUUGAUCUACCAUCUAACCCAAAAAUACCCUGAGUUUCCAUCAUGAAGUGGGAUAAGGUGAAGUUCACCUGUCACUUCUCCUUUUAUCAGGAUGAUGGUGUCACAGUGACUCCUUUGAUGACUUUCAUGCUGUAGUUUGUUUCUCUGCUGACCUAAUAAACACAUUUAAUC